GUCCCUAGCAACACCCUGCAGCGUUUGAAAUCUGAGGGGAAAAGACUGUAGUCAGCCCUUAGUGGAUGAGAGCGCCUAUGCUCCAGAAACAGCAGGCUCCCAGGAUGGACACCCCGCCCCCUGAAGAACGCUUAGAGAAGCAAAAUGAAAAACUGAACAACCAGGAAGAGGAGACGGAGUUUAAGGAACUGGACGGUCUGAGGGAAGCCUUGGCAAACCUCCGGGGACUGUCAGAGGAGGAGAGGAGCGAGAAGGCUAUGCUUCGCUCCCGCAUUGAAGAGCAGUCCCAGCUCAUCUGCAUCCUGAAGCGGAGGUCAGAUGAGGCCCUGGAGCGCUGCCAGAUCCUAGAGCUGCUCAAUGCAGAGCUGGAGGAGAAGAUGAUGCAGGAGGCUGAGAAGCUCAAGGCCCAGGGUGAGUACAGUCGGAAACUAGAGGAACGCUUUAUGACCCUAGCAGCCAACCACGAGUUGAUGCUCCGCUUCAAGGAUGAAUACAAGAGUGAGAACAUCAAGCUGAGGGAGGAGAAUGAGAAGCUGAGGCUGGAGAAUAGCAGCCUCUUCAGCCAGGCUCUGAAGGAUGAGGAGGCGAAAGUAUUACAGCUCACAGUCCGGUGUGAGGCCCUCACUGGGGAGCUAGAAACGCUGAAGGAGAGGUGUGCUCAGGAUGCCUGCCAGGCACAGGCGCGCGAGAAGGAGCUGCUGGAGCUACAGAGCCAGCAGGCCUGCACCCACACCAAGGAGACAGAACAGCUGCGCAGCCAGCUGCAGACCCUCAAGCAGCAGCACCAGCAGGCUGUGGAGCAGAUAGCUAAGGCAGAGGAGACACACAGCAGCCUGAGCCAGGAGCUGCAGGCCAGGCUGCAGACCGUCACUAGAGAGAAAGAGGAGUUGCUGCAGCUGUCCAUUGAAAGGGGCAAAGUGCUUCAGAACAAACAGGCAGAGAUCUGCCAGCUUGAGGAAAAGUUGGAGAUAGCAAAUGAAGACAGGAAGCAUGCGCUGGAGCGGUUUGAGCAAGAGGCAGUGGCUGUGGACAGCAACUUGAGAGUCAGGGAGCUUCAGCGCAAAGUAGAUGGGAUCCAGAAGGCCUACGAUGAACUCAGGCUGCAGUCUGAAGCCUUCAAAAAGCACAGCUUGGAUCUUUUAAGCAAGGAGAGAGAACUCAAUGGCAAACUCCGCCAUCUCUCUCCAUAGGGAAGUUUCUGCUUCCUCUGGCCUGCAAUUCAGAAUUCAAAUAUUUGCGUCUUAGCAUUAUGGCAAGAGUAAAGAUGAUAUCCCAUUUAUUAUACUUUCAAGCACAAAAGGCAACUCAAAGAAAAGCUACUUUACUAUGAUAUUGUUGUUAUUAUUGUAAAGCCAUUAUUAAUUUUCAUUUCUACACCUAGAAUACACAAGAUUUGCCAGAUUUCCUUCUGUGCCUUAGAAAUCUUAAAUUUACUAGUAGUAUCUUCUCCUACCCAUAAGUUAUUAAUUCUCAACCUCAGAUAUCUUCAUUUAUGUUAGGAUUUUAAAUUAGCAGCUUCUAUGAUUUAAGUCAAUCUAAGUGCAGUGAGAUGUGCCAUUGUGAAAAAUAAUUAGCACAAUUACCCACUGUAGAUAGUUAGGCUUAUAGUCUCCCAUAGUUGAGAUUGUAAGCAAACAUGUAUCAGCAUAAUAGCAUGAAUGCUUUGCAGAAAAAAAAAAGUGUCUGACUUUAUUUUAUUUUGCGCUAGCUUGGAAAAUGAUUGAGAUCAAGUUCUUUAACAAAGAAGGUCAAUUUUAUUCUGUAUGAGCAAUAUGAUUCAAAUAAGUUAUACAAAACAACUUUUAUUUUUUCUGCAAGCUUAGAUAAUAUUCCAUUUUUUGGUUUUCUCUUUAAAAAGAGGAUUUAGAUGUGCAAUAAUGCAAAUAUCAGUAGCUUAAUUUAAUAUUGCACGAUAUGCUAAUAGACAAUUAGACAAUUUGGGGUAACAAAUCAUAGCAGACGUGAUCUAUAGAGUAACUCAGAAAUUGUUUUGUUUCUAUUAGCAUAUUUUUUGUAAUUAAGAUUUUCCUUUUUUAAAAAAAUCUAAGCUGAACGUGUGUAUGUAUGCUUGCAGCAUUUUUGUAGUAAUACCUACAUUUUGUAAGAAUAGUUAUAAAAACAUGAUAUAUAUAUAUGUAAAGUUCUUAAAAAAGUUCUCAAAGGUAGUUAUAUUUUCUUAUCUUCCUGUAAUUAGGUAUUGAUAUAUAAACAUUAUUAUGAAUACCUCUCAAAAUAGAUUGUAAUGUAAUAUUUUUCUCACCCAUUUUGCUGAAGGCUACCAAGUUACAUAAUGAAUUUACUUAAAAAAUAUGACUUGGUGCCUUUUUAGUAAAACCAUUUCCAAGCAA